AGAACACAGGAGACUGAGGAAGUAGCAAUGCAGAGUUUGAGUGAGGGAGAAACAAAGCGACAGGUUUCUGGAACUAUUUUGGACUCCCGUAGUAACUUUUAACUCUGCUACAAUGCCCAUGUACUUGGUCUUUUAAGCUCUCUCUGGCUUUUGAUCUCUUUUUUUUUUUCCUCCUACAUGAAACAGAAGACAGAGUUACAGGAAAUGAAGGGUAUAGGAGGAAAGAAAGAGCUGUAGUUAUCGUAGAUGCCAGAGUGGUAAGAGGCAGCUCUUCUUUCAGGGGCUUAGCUGAGGGCCAGAGUAGUACAGCUCGUCUCCACGGGGGUGGAGAGGGGUGCCUCAAAACAAAAGUGAACAUUUCUCUCUUCUAAGUCGGCUUCUAAUGGCCCUGGUUUUUGUCUGUUUUAACCUAAAAGGUUAUUGCACUAUUAACAGGUAAAAAAUUCUCUUCUGACCAAAUACAUGUAUUUCUAGCAUAAUAUAUUCUCUCUCUCUCUCUGGAUAAAAUUUAUUAGCAUAUCAGCAUAAACAUAAUUUUUGUAAGGUCAGACAAGAGAUUUGAAGUGUAAUUCAAGGGGAAUUUGUAUUAACGUAAUGAAACAUUCUGCUGUGAAGUUUACUAGCAAUGCCUCACUCUGGGUUAUCAUUUCUGACUCCUCCCAUUUCCUUUCUCACCCGUCACCUGGCCUUCAUUCAUUCUCUGUCCUAGAAGAUAACCUCUAAAACCAGUGACAGUCCAUCCAGCCUGCUGUUAAAAAAAAAAAAAAAAAAAAAAAAAAUGUUGCUCACUCUGUCCCGGCCAGUCUGGCUCUAGCGUCAGCUCAAAGGGGCCCAGGUACAGCUCGGGCUGCCACUCCAUAGGGUGCAAGCUGUAAGCCUUGGUGGCUUCCAUGGGGUGCUAAUCCUGCAGACACACAGAAUGCAAGAGUGAAGAAGUCUUGACAACUUCCACCUAGAUUUCAGAGGAUAUUUCAGAAAGCCUACAUACCCAGGCAGAAGCCUGUCGCGCGGCGUAGCCAACACAAAAACUCUACUAGGGCAGUGCUGAGGGGAAAUAUGGGGUUGUGCCCCCACACAGAGUGCCCAACAGGGCACUGCCUAGUGGAACUGUAGGAAGGGGGCCACUGUCCUCCAGACCCCAGAAUGGUAGAGCCUCUGGCAGCUUGCACCCUACAUCUGGAAAACCCACAGGCAUUCAACUCCAACCCGUGAGAGCAGCCAGCGAGGCUGCACCCUGCAAAGCCACAGAGGCAGAACUGUCCGAGGCCUUGGGAGCCCACUCCUUGCACCAGUGAGCUCCAUAACUUGAUCUUGAACUUCCAGCCUCCAAAACCAUGAGAAAUAAAUUUCUGUUGUUUACAAGUAUGUUAGUCCAUUUGCAUUGCUAUAAAAGAAUACCUGACACUGGGUGAUUUAUAAAGAAAAGAGGUUUAAUUGGUUCACAGUUCUGCAGGCUAUACAGGAAGCAUGGUGUAAACAAUCUCAAAAGAGAUUGUUUUGGAGCUUUAAGACUUAAUGACUGCCUUGCUGGGUUUCAGACCUGUGUGGGGCCUGCUUCCCCUUUCUUUUGGCCGACUUCUCCUUUCUGGAAUGGGAAUGUUUAUCCAGUGCCUGUACCACCAUUGUAUCUUGGAAGUAAAUAACUUUUUUUAUUUUACAGGCUCAUUAGUGGUAGGAGAUGAGUCUCUUACGAGACUUAGGACUUUAGACUUGAUGCUGGAACAAGUUAAGACUUUUGGGGACUUUGGGGAAAGUAUGAUUGUAUUUUGCAAUGUGAGGACGAGAUGUGGGGGGCCAGCGGCAGAAUGAUAUGGUUUGGAUAUUUGUCCCCUCCAAAUCUCAUGUUCCAGUGUGAUUCCCAGUGUCAGAGGCGGGACCUGGUAGAAGAUGAUUGGAUCGCAGCAGUGGAUCCUUCACAAAUGGGUUUGCACCAUCCCCUUGGUGAUAAGUGAAUUCUCACUCAGUUAGUUAAUAUGAGAUCUGGUUUUUUGAAAGAGUCUUGGACUUCCCCUUCUCUCUCUCUUGCUCCCACUCUCACCAUGGGAUGUGCCUGCUCCCCCUUCGCCUUCCACCACGAUUGUAAGCUCCCUGAGGCCCUGACCAGAAGCAGAUGCCGGCACUAUGCUUCCUAGACAGCCUGCAGAACUGUGAACCAAUUAAACCUCUUUUCUUUAUAAAUUACCCAGUCUUGGGUAUAUCUCUAUAGCAAUGCAAAUGGACUGACAUUCUUGUAAACAACAGAAAUUUAUUUCUCAUGGUUUUGGAGGCUGGAAGUUCAAGAUCAAGUCAUCAACAAAUUCAGUGUCUGGUGAGGGCACAUUUGCUGUUUCAUGGAUGGCUGUAUUUUGUUGGAUCCUCAUGUGGUGGAAGGGACUAAUGAGCUCCCUACAAGGGCAUUAAUCCCAUUCAUGAGGGCUCUACCCUCAUAAUCUAAUCACCUCCCAAAAGCCCCACAUCCUAAUGCCUUCACCUCGGGGGUUAGAAUUUCAACAUGUAAAUGUUUGGUGGACACAAACAUUCAGACCAUAGCACCUGGUUUCCCUGACAUUACUCUCUUGCAAUACCCAUCUAUCAAAAAAUAGACAAUACUUUUCUCCUGAGUAUCAGGUUCAUAAACUGUCACAUCUCAGGAAACCAUGGCAGGGCCUUUUAUUCCCUAAAUUCAGAAGCACCCUUAUCCGUCCAUCAGUAAGUCUAGCCCCUCAGCCACUCUAUUCCUUAUCAUUCUACUCUCCUGGCAGUUCUCAUACUACAGACACCACUUCUCCUUGGCAUUCCUGAUAUAUAAGUCAGUUCUUUCCUUUCUCCUCCUUUGUAUACUAGUAGUAGAACCUUUUAUGACUCUUGCCUGAAGUUCUCAUCCUCACAGUUUUGUUCUCUCUUUGAUCUUCUGUUCCUUUAACAUGAGGUUCCAAAUUGGUUUCCUUUAUGAUAGACCUCACUAAGUAAUGAAAAAUUUCAGUUUCUCUAAGUAUGUUUUUCUGGACUUUAUGCCCUAUUCUUUUGCAUUUCUAUCUUUUUGUUUGGGUAAGCUUUUCAUUCUAGUUAAAAACUAGUUCUUUCCUAAACACAGUCUUCAGAACAAAAAACCUUAAUCAAAUAGAUAUCCUCUAAUAUAUCUUAGGUAUAUGAAAAGUGGCUCAUUGUGACAUCCAAUUGCUGGUGGAGAAGAGCCCCAAAAAGGAACGAAGAUAUGAGGCCAAGGUGGGCAGAUCACCUGAGGUCAGGAGUUCAAGACCAGCCUGGCCAACAUGGUGAAAUUCUGUCUCUAUUAAAAAUACAAAAAUUAACUGGGCAUGAUGGCACAUGCCUGUAAUCCCAGCUACUUAGGAGGCUGAGGCAGGAGAAUUGUUUGAACCCAGGAGGUGGAGGUUGCAAUGAGCCAAGAUCACGCCACUGCACUCUAGCCUGGGCAACAGAGCAAGACUCCAUCUUCUCCAUCUUAAAAGAAAAAAAAAAAAAAAAAAAGGAAUGAAGACAGAAAUUCAAAAAAAUGCUUAAAGUCCCUGCCCCUAAAAAGGUUAUAGUCUAGUUUGGAGGAGAUAUAUUCAGUAUAUGUUUUUAGGAAGUUUAUUAUGCAAUGCAAAAUAGCAUUCAUGCACUGAGGCUGUAAAUAACAAAGGAGAAUUCACUAUCAGCAGCAUCAAUCUUCCUUGGCUGGAAACUAGAAAAGUCCAUUGCUACCUCCUUGCUGCAUUUUACAAUUUACUUUGUUAUUUUCCAACUGUGCUUGGCCUCAAAAUGCUACUGCUGUGAAGUUAGUUUGAUGAAAACAGUCUUUUCAAGUUUCCAUAUGGUUUCAAAUUAUUACUCAUCUAACUAAUAAUCAGUUUGAAAAAAUAAGUUUGCACACAAUGCCAAUUCAGCAGUGGGGAAAAUUAAAAGACUGGCCUUUUUCUCUUGCUCCCACCCCCUCUUCCAAAACUUGUCAGCCACACUUGGGAAGGAGUUCAUGAGGUAGGUUUUGAGAUAAAAUUUAAGCCCAAGCCCUUUUUAAAAUGCUAAUUGUUUUCCUGUAUUGCAAAUAGAUGUCUAGGCAAUAAGUAUUAAUUGCAUAAUUUCUUAUAUUAUUGAUAAUAAAGAGAUGGAAGUCAGUAUAAAAGUGGGAAUGUAAUUGGAUUUGUUCAGAAUCUGGUAUGAUGGGUUCCUGUGUGUAGAGAGGAGGGAGCAGAGAACUGAGAAUCAACACAUAGAGGAAGGACAGAACAUGAUAUAAGUGCGGCCAAGGUAAGACGACCAACAUGGCUGGAACAGAGAAUUCCUUUUGAAAAGAAGAGGGAGAUUGCAAAACUGGAGGGUCUUGGCUCGUGUCCAGAUGCCUCGAUCUGGUGCUCAAUAGAAAGGCAUUGUUAACUCUGGAGCAGUGGCAUGACAUAAUGGAGGCCGUGUCUCAGGAGGAUGAAUCGCACAUUGAUGUCCCAGAAUCUUGGAGAGGAAGAUCCUAGAGAUCAUUGCUGUGCGUUCCAAGGGUGGAAGGGAAAUCACUGCAGCUGCACCCACUGUCCACUGUUGACUUUGUCUUAAAGCAGUGACAAAAGCCCUUGGGAGCUGUUUGGUUGCUUUUUUAAAAAAUCAAGCUAGUUUGAGUUGGGUUUCUGUCUCUCCAAAAUCAGAAUCUUAACAAUUAAUUGCUUUUUGGAGUUAUAUGAGUUGCCUUAGGCUUUCAAAGAGACAUAAUAUUUUAGGAAAACAGAAUUAGGAGUAGAUAUAGAGGCAGGAAUGAAUCACAUGAUUGUUCAUGGGACAAUGACUUGUCCACUUUCAUGAGAACAGAGGGGUCUUCUUUGAGACCAUAUUAAAGAGGUUACUGGAGCCAGAUGGUGGCCUCUGCUAAACCAUUUCUCUAGCCCUGCUAUUGCUGCUGGUGUUUAGGUAUUCAUUUUUGCUACAGCAGUGUGCUUGAGACUCAGUGGAAUUAGUUUCCAAACUGGCGGAACCCCUCCUCUGCAAAAUCUGAUAUUCUUUUUAUUGUUGACCUAUUUGGGGCUCCUUUGGUUUUUUUAGAUACAGUUUUCUACCUGCUAUCAAUAUACAUCUAUUAUGUCUAAAACUAAAUUUACAAAAUCCUUCCCACCAAACUACAAUUUCUCUUGUGUUCCCUGUAACUGUUAGUGGCAAUGCCAUCCUCUCCAUCCCCCAGAUAACCUUGGUGUUCUUGGAUGUUCCUCUCCAUUGCGUGCUCUCCCUAAUCAUUCCAAUGUUGUCUCUGGAUUUUCCCUCCAACGCAGUGUCUGCUUCUUGCCUUCAGAUUCACUCCCUACCUGCCUUUCUGUUUUCUCUUGUCUCCAGCUUCCACCCUCCCUUGUUCUUGUACAAAUAGGAAUAUAGUCCUCCAGAAGCCCAUAGCUCAUCAGGUCCAUGAUGUAUAAAAGGUGGGCAUUUAAUAUCUUGUCAUUUUAUUCCUUCUGUUUAAAAAUCUUCAAUUAAUACCUACCACCAGUCAAAUGAAGUCUAAAAGUAGCCUUCCCUCAUUAGGAGUCAAACUUCACAACUUAAUUUCUGCUUCUUCCUGCUGCCUGUACUUCAGAAAAAAAAAACAAACUGUUGGAUUUCCUUGUGAGAGUGACUUUUCCUUGUCUGCAUAUUGUGCUUCUGCCUUUCCUUGUGUUUCUCAUGACCUUAUGGCAUCUCUGACUCCAAAUUGUAUGUAUCCAGCACAAAUCUCAAUCCUUCCACAAUAAUCAUUGUAUAACUACAGUGUUUCUUUGGACAGAGAGGUAGCACCAAUGGCUGUGAUGCAGUAAUGAAAGUUUUGAUUUCUCCAAUCCAAAGGACUGUUUUAUUUUUACUGUUUUAUAUAACAAAUAGAAAUAUAAUUUACAUUUCUAGUUUCUCGUACUGAAAUAUAUUUCUGACAGCUAUAAUAUUUUUCUACUUAACUAGAAAAGACAUAGUGCCCUCCCCAUACACAAGGGUGUCAUGCUUAUUUCUUCCACACAACUUCUCUGAGUCUCCUCUUUACAAUUAGAAGAGGUUUCUGAAUUCCUUAGACACCUUCUUUAUGACACAAUAUCCUUUAUGACAUGUAUUGUUCUGUGUUUAUGUACUGAACUUAAGUUCCCAAUAAAGCCUAAAUCCUUUGAGAACAUAAAAUCUGGUAUUAGGUUUUACACAUAGUAACAGCUCAAACAUUUGAAGAUAGUAAAUCCACUGAUUUUUAUUAUCCACUCUGUAUCUCACAUCUUUGCUACAAGGAUAUGAAUAAAACUUUUAAAAUUGUUUAAAUGCUUACCAAAAUAAUAUAAUUCAUUAAAAUUGUAUAAUGAGCUCAAUCCCACCUCUCCCAUCCCCUAUCUGCCCCCUCAGUAGCUACCACUUUUUUUGUUGUUGAGACAGGGUCUCACUCUGUCACCCAGGGUAAAGUGCAGUGGCACAAUCACGGCUCACUGCAGCCUCGAACCCCUGAGCUCAAGUGAUCCUCCCACCUCAGCAUCCUGAGCAGCUGGAACCACAGGUGCACACCACCAUACCCGGCUAAAUUUUUUGUUUUUUUUUGUAGAGAUGGGGUCUCCCUAUGUUGUCCAGGCUGGUGUCAAACUGCGGCUCAAGUGAUCCUCCCACCUCAGCCUCCCAAAGUGCUGGAUUACAGGAGUGAGCCACCAUACCCAGCCUACCACUUCUAACUGUACCCAGUUUUAGUGUAGUGGUUACUUCAUUAUCUGUAAAAAUGUGUGUAUCUUGCUCUUUUUGUUUAUCAGUAUUAAACCUUAUCUCUCAACUUCCUGUUUUGAUGGAAAAGAAUCAACUCCCUUAUACUAACUCCCUCCUUCCCUCUCUUCCUUUUAACAGGCGUAUCUUUCUAGUUCCUAUUUUCAUGCAUUUGUUUAUUGCCUCUUUUAAGUAAUACAGCAACAUAAAUUUCUAAUGAAAUCACUUUGACUCCCCACUUUUUAGGGUAAGAAAUUAGUAACCGCUGCCAUUUUACCUCCCCCUUUGUUUUUUCUUUAAUAAUGUCUGCUCUCUUUUUCAGUUUAGAAUGCCUAUCCAUUUGAUAUAGAAGUACCUGGCUGAGGCCGGACACAGUGGCUCACGCCUGUAAUCCCAGCACUUUGGGAGGCCAAGGCAGGCAGAUCACAAGGUCAGGAGAUCAAGACCAUCCUGGCUAACACGGUGAAACCCCGUCUCUACUAAAAAUACAAAAAAUUAGCUGGGCAUGGUGGCAGGCGCCUGUAGUCCCAGCUACUCGGGAGGCUGAGGCGAGAGAAUGGCAUGAAUGUGGGAGGUGGAGCUUGCAGUGAGCCAAGAUCGCGCCACUGCACUCCAGCAGAGGCGACAGUGCGAGACUCCGUCUCAAAAAAAAAAAAAAAAAAAAAAAAAAAAAAGAAGUACCUGGCUGACACAUGUCAUGUUUUUCCCUCUUAUACCUAUUCUGUUUUUGAAUUUUGGUAUCUUGAUGCUAUCUUACUUUGGUCCCUUAAUGCUUUAUCUCUUUUGGUUAAAUAUAUAGGUCUUGGCCAGGCACUGUGGCUCACACCUGUAAUCCCAGCACUUUGGGAGGCCCAGGCAGGUAGAUCACCUGAGCUCAGGAGUUCAAGACCAGCCUGGCCAACAUAGUGAAACCCUGCCUCUAAAAAUACAAAAAUUAACCAGGCAUGGUGACACGUGCCUGUAAUCCCAGCUACUUAGGAGACUGAGGCAGAAGAAUCACUUGAACCUGGGAGGCGGAGGUUGCAGUGAGCCAAGAUUGCACCACUGCACUCCAGCCUGGGCAAUACAGCAAGACUCUGUCUCGGGGGGAAAAAAAUUGUAUAUAUAUCAUUGAGAAGGUGACAUUCAAGUUAAAUCUUAAAGGGAGAGAGUCACUUGGCUAACUGGGGUACAGCAUCCCAGGCAGAGGGAACACUAGGGCACAGGUUUCUCAUGGGGGCUUGGAGUGGGGCUGGACUAGGGUGAGGGAAGGAGAAGAGAGGAUCGGGGAGGUGUGUGGGUCAGGUCCUGAAGUGCCUGAUAGGCUAUUGCAAGGAUUUGGACUCUGAAAAAAUUGGGGGAUAAGUAGGGUUUCCUUCUCCAUAACAUUGUGAUUCUUUUUCAUGGGUGCUACCUUCUUUCUCUGAAGACAUUAAUUCAUAGGAUUUAGAUUUUGUUUUUCUUGUUUGCAUAUUUGUCUUUUGUUUUCAUCUGUUCACUAAAGCCAGUUUCCCUGGGAUUUUACUUUCUUGUUGGUUCAUCUUGGUCUUUUCUUUCAGACUUCAAGUUUUCUUCAAAGAAAUGGCAAUCCUUGGUUGUUAUUUCAUAUUUAAGAAUGAGGGACUGGGCCAGGCACAGUGGCUUGUGCCUAUGAUCUUAGCACUUUGAGAGGUAAAGGCAGGUGGAUCACUUGAGGUCAGGAGUUCAAGACCAGCCUGGCCAACAUGGUGAAACCCUGUCUCUAAGAAAAAUAUAAAAAUUAGCCAGGCAUGGUGUUGUGCGCCUGUAAUCCCAGCUACUUAGGAGGCUGAGACAAGAGAAUCACUUGAACCUGGGAGGCAGAGGUUGCAGCGAGCCAAGAUUGCGUUACUGCACUGCACUCCAGCCUGAGCGACAGAGUAAGGCUCCAUCUCAAAACAAAAAAAAAAAAAGAAUGAGGGGCUAGAGAAAAAAUAAUAAGGGACUGGAGUAGCUGCUCCUCAUCUUUGUACGUUCAUGGAUAGGGAGUUGGCACUUUUCCUGGGACUACCAUAUUCAAAAUGGAAGGAUGAGGAUUUACUCUGGGGCUCCAUAACUAGCUACCACGGUUGUAUAUAACUAGCUGCCACGGUUAUAUAUAACUAGUUACCACAGUUUCCUGCACCCAAGUUGUUCAGUUAUUUUAGCAAUGACCCCUCUGAUGCUUUUCCCUAUUAACUGCCUGUAAUUUGGGUCUGAGCCAGGGCGAGUGAGGAGGAAGUGUCAAGAUUUCUCACAGCCACAUCUUUAAUUAAAUCUAGUGUUUUCGGAAACUUCUCACCCACUCCUCCUGUAGCACCUCACUGGACUUCUGACAAACGGGUCGGUGUUUUCUUAUCCCCCGUUGAUGCCUAUAUUCAAGAUUAUGGCUUCCCUUGCUUUGCUGCAUGAGUAAAUAUUGUACUUUACUUUCCGCUUUCCGUUUUUCCAUAUUUCAGAAAGUUUCAGAAAUCAGUCUUCUGUUGAUGGUUUCCCUCCAUUAUUGUAGCAGGAUUAUCACUUCUUUUGUACAUAUUCAUUUUAAAGACCUUAGAAAGAAAGGAGAAGCAAACAUUUGUGCUCCCAUUCUCCAUCCUGAACUGAAAGCCUUUCACAUUUCAUUGACGGUUUUGCUGAAAUUAGAGAAUACUAUAUUUUUGACACUCCUUUUAUCUAUCUGCUAAUAAAUCUAUCGACAACAAAACUAGUUGUCAUUAAUAUUUUAUUUUAAUGUCAUGCCAGCCGCUAAUAUCCACUUAACUUUUUUUUGAAAUGGGGUCUCUCUAUGUUGCCCAAGCUGGUUUCAAACUCCUGGCCUCAGUCCAUCCUCCCACAUUAGCCUCCAGAGUGGCUGGAACUACAGGCACAUGCCACCAUACCUGGCUUCCACUUAACUUUUCUAAAUGCUUAAGAUUAUUUAUUUUAAAAGUCAACUAUAGGAUGUUACUAAGAAUCUGUGAAGCAAUUAUGAUAAGAAUCAUUUAUACUAAAUGUUUCAAUCAACAACCCAUUAGAUAAAUUGGCAAAAUGUACAUACAAACAGCUAAUUCACAAAACAAGAAAAAUUUUAAUAAGUGCUUAAAUAUAUGAAAAUACACUCAGCUUUACUCUUAAGAAGAAAAUGCAAAUGAAACUGUAGUGGAAUAUUUUUUAACCUUUUACAUUUGCAAAGAUCAAAAAGUUUAGCGCUAGUCACGAUUAAAAUGAUGAUUGUUAUUUUGUGUGCCAGCUAUUAUGCUAGGUACUUCAAAAUAUAAAUAUUUUUAAGGCUAACACUUUAUUAGUGAGAAGAUAUAGACACUGUUGAAUAUUUGGGUAUGCAUCACAAAAUGUCUACCGAGGGCAAUUUGGCAAUAGCUGUAACAUUUUUUCUAUCAUACCUUUUGACACAGCAGUUCCAUUUCCAGAAAAUUAUUCACACAUGUAAUAAACAUAUAAGGACAUUUGUUGCAAUGUUGUUAGUAUUUGCAAAAGACUGAAAUAUACCUACAUGCCCCAUCAGUAAGGAACUGGUUAAAUAACAUUUCAUCCUUACGAUGUAACUUUAUGCAGUCAUUAAAAAGUAUGAGGAAGAUCUAUGGGUACUGAAAGAACACCAAGAUAAAAUAAGUUAAAAAAAAAGCAAGGUGCAGAAUAGCAUGCUGUCUAUCAUUUGUGGUUCAAAAAUGCACACGUUUACAUACGCACAGUCUCUCCCAGGAAGGACACACAAGUUGCUGGGAAGAGUAGGUGCCUUUGUGGAGAGAAACUGGGUCACCAUGAAACAGGGGUAAAAAGAAAAUUUGUUUUUCCAUUUGUAACUUUUAAAUUUUAUACUUAUGCUUAUAGUGCCUAUUCAGAAAUAAAUAUGUAGACAGAUAAAUGAAAUUUAUAGUUGUCCAAACAAAAAUAUAUGUAUCAGAAUUGUAAAUGGAAGAUCAUUCUUCUUGACUUGUAAAAAUCUAGUUUGGGAGAUUCUGAGUUUAUGAAAUUGGAAAAGCUAAAGGGUUUCCCAGCCAUCCUGUCUCCAUUGCUCACUCCUGCACUUCCGCACUCCAUUCUAUUUCCUUCUUUUGGUCACUGUGAGGCCUCUCUUUAUUUGUACUAUGGCUGCUGUCCAGCCCUCUUCCAUCUCUAUAGCCCAACUCUUUGCUUCCCAAGUAUCGUGGCCUGUGUCUGCCAGCCACGGAGCCACUGAAUAGGCAGCACUCCAAAAACAAGCGUCUAUGAGGCCCCAGAUCUUGGUGAAUCCAGGUGCCAACAUGGUUUUCACUACAGUUUCAGGAACACUCUACUUUCACAGACCCACCCAUGACCACAGCAAUCCCAUUGCCAGGCAUUUAUUCUAUGAAGACCCUCUGAUGAAACAUAUCCUAUCUUCAGACACUUCUAAACCUUUGUUGAUCAAGACUGUGGCUUUAAAAUGAUCAGAGACUUUUUAAAAAAUAAUUGUAGAUGUAAAACUACCUCUACUUCUACUACCAUAAGGAAGCUUAGUGAUUUUUUUUAUGCCUUUAGCUUAGAUUAACAUGUGGGUAGACUCAAACACAGGGACUCAUCACUGUAAUUAGAAGGGAACACACCUUCUUGGACUGAACCACAGUGAAACACUUGUUUUCCUUCACCUGAGACACAGCUGAAUCAUAGCUUCUACCUUCAGCUACUUAUUUACCUGGACUUGCAUGUGAUGUGCCUGAAUACAAUACAUUCCCAGCAGGAGCGGCAAAGGGCCAGUGAUGUGACAAGAGAAAGGUGUAUUGAGUUUAGCUGAAACUCACAGAGACUAUCUCCAGCAGGAAUGAUACUUGACUCCACAUAAGAGUUCUAAUUCUGAAAAAUUGUGAAAUGAGAAUUUAAGUCAUCAUCAAACUAAUGAUGUCUGGGAAGUGACAAAUAUUAGAUGGCUGAUAGGGAUUGUACAACCUGUUUUUGUAUGUAUAAAUUGUGUAACAGUGUGUGGCAGUGUUUUAUUGAAACAAGAUUGUCCUAGCCAGUAAUAAAAAUGCUGUUCCCUGGCUGGGCAUGGUGGUUUAUGCUUUGUAAUCCCAGCACUUUGGGAGGCCGAAGCAGGUGGAUCACUUGAGGCCAGGAGUUCGAGACCAGCCUGGCCAACACAGCGAAACCCCGUCUCUACUAAAAAUACAAAAAUUAGCCAGACAUGGUGGCAGGCACCUGUAAUCCCAGCUACACGGGAGGCUGAGGCAGGAGAAUCACUUGAACCUGGGAGGUGGAGGCUGUAGUGAGCAGAGAUCACGCCAUUGCACUCCAGCCUGGGUGACAAGAGUGAAACUCCAUCUCAAAAAAAUAAAUAAAUAAAAAUAAAAAUGCUCUCCCCUAAUAGGUGAAGUCAGGUUUAGUUGUUAUAAGCAUGACUGUCUCACUGCUUUGAAAUUUCUACUAAAAGCCUUUCAGGCAGGGACCAUAACUGAUGCUUAAAGUGGGUUGGAGAUGGGAGGAGAAAUAACCUGCCAAGGCCAAGUAAAGGUUGGUCCUGUGUCUCCAGCAUUUUCUACUGCUUCUGUGGAUACUUACACCUGCCAGCUCACUUACCUGUCUCAUCUACAAAGCUCUGAGCACCCUGACAACAGGGACAAGUCCAGUAAAUAUUUGUUGAAAAAGGAGGAUUGGUUUUUUGGUUUGUUUUUUCAGUUGACUCUUUUAGUCAAAGUCCGUAACAGGGCUUUGUCUUCUGGUUAAAAAAUAAAUAAAAACUGAUUUCCUUAUUUUCAUGAUUUAAAUGAAACCUGUUCAGCUUCGUUGACCGUAACUUUAAAGUUACUAAGUGGCCUGGUUCAGCUUCAUUGACAGUAACUUAAAAGUUUCCAAAAGGCCUUGAGGAAGCAUUCCAUUUCCCCUCCCACGCUGCUCACUCAAACACACGCUAGCCUCUGCUGCUUGAAUUCUACAUAGUUUCAGUCUGCUGCUGACAAGACCUCCAAGCUACCUCUCUCUGAAUGUCUAAAGUGAAGCGGUUUCCUUUCUUCUUCAGCUCAGAGGCUGAGAAUGGUGUGGAGGAGAAAAAGAAAGCCUGCAGGUCGCCAACAGCCCAAUCCCCUACCCCAUCUGUGGAGGCGGACUCCCCAGACCAGAAGAAAAUCAUUAGCCUAUGGUCAAAAUCCAGUUUUGAUGGUGCCUCUUUAGCAAGUGAUAAGAACGACUGUAAAACAGAAAGCAAAAAUGACCCUAAGACUGAAAGAAAAAAGUCUUCAUCUUCCAGCCAGUACAAGGCCAAUAUGCACUUUCACAAGUUGUUUCUUAGUGUCCCAACGGAGGAACCACUGAAGCAAAGCUUUACCUGUGCUCUACAGAAAGAAAUACUAUACCAAGGAAAGCUCUUUGUAUCAGAAAACUGGAUUUGUUUUCAUUCCAAAGUCUUUGGAAAAGACACAAAGAUCUCUAUUCCAGCUUUCUCGGUAACCCUAAUAAAGAAAACCAAAACUGCUCUUCUAGUGCCAAACGCCCUGAUCAUAGCAACAGUCACAGACAGGUACAUAUUUGUCUCCUUACUCUCCAGAGAUUCAACUUACAAACUACUAAAAUCUGUGUGUGGACACUUAGAAAAUACAAGUGUUGGUAACAGUCCCAAUCCAUCUUCUGCUGAAAACAGUUUCCGAGCAGACCGCCCUUCAUCUCUGCCUCUGGAUUUCAAUGAUGAAUUCUCAGAUCUGGAUGGAGUGGUUCAACAAAGAAGGCAAGACAUGGAAGGAUAUAGCAGUUCUGGUUCUCAAACUCCUGAAUCUGAGAACUCUCGAGUAGAUUUCCAUGCGACAGAAUCCCAAACAGUUCUGAAUGUCUCCAAGGGAGAAGCAAAGCCAACUCGGGCAGAUGCCCAUGUGAACAGAGUACCUGAAGGAAAAGCCAAGAGUCUCCCUGUACAGGGUCUGUCAGAAACUGUUGGAAUCUUACAUAAAGUCAAGUCUCAGAAAUGUCCGAUGCUUCACCAUAUUCUUAUAUUCUAUGCAAUUGUUGUCUGUGCACUAAUCAUCUCGACCUUCUACAUGAGAUACAGAAUUAAUACUCUGGAGGAGCAGCUGGGGUUACUAACCUCCAUUGUGGACACCCAUAAUACUGAACAGGCAGCACCAUCUGGCCUGAGGUCACAAGUACAAUUCAAUGUGGAGGUUCUCUGUCAAGAGCUUACAGCUAACAUAGUGAAAUUAGAAAAGAUACAAAAUAACUUACAGAAGUUGCUUGAGAAUGGUGACUGAUCGACCAGAUUGCUUGGGCCAUCGGAAUACCUCAUGUUUCCCUUUGAAGAAGGUGCUUCCUGAGGCGUUUUGUUUGAGUGCACCCUGCUGGUCAGAGGUGCAAGCAGAUGAGAAUCCAGACAUUGCAUGUGGAGGUCUCCAGCUCAGGAAAGUGAGGAGGGAAAUAAUUUUGGUUCUUGUGCAAUAAAAGUUGACCUUGACUCUCUGAGGAAGAUUUUGCUGCUUUUGCCUGAAGAAAACAGACCCAUCUCUGGAGGUCUCAGGAAGGGCCCAGCGAACACACUCUCUUGGAUAAUUACCACGAUGGCGUCAGCAAACACUCCACCCUGUGCCUUUUUAGUCCUUCCCGCCCUCCUGCCUCUCCCUUACACCCCUCUUAACGACUUUCAAACUAAAGGAUACAUCAUAUACUGACAAACUCAAUGUGGUCCUUUCAAGAAUUAGCCAUGAGUCUCAAAAAGGCAAUAAAUGGCUCUAAGUGGACAGGUUUGCUUCAAACAAGUAACAUCUACAUUUUGUCUUUUUUUUUUCAGUUCUCCUGUUAUGUUCUGGUUGAAAUCACCUGUGUGUCUUAAUUUCUCAAUUCCUUUUUGGCAAGAAUAUCAAGCAAGGUGAAUUUAACAUUAUGUUUAUGUUUUGUUUUGUUGCUGUAACUAAUAGUUAAUUGGACUGAUUCUUACCCAGCCCUGGUCAAGAAUCUGUGAGGCAUGUGACUGAAGUACUAAAUUAAACUUAUUUUGAAACCAAACCUAAUUUUUAAGCCAAAAGGUGUAAUAGUGAUUUAAUACAGGAUGAAAAACACUGAAUUUUUAAGACUGUAGGUGGACUAUGUUAGUAGUUUUCAAGCAGGAUGUCUGUAUUCAGCAUUCAAUAAUGCUAAAAUCCCUUUCAGCAUGAAAUUUGUAUGUUUUUAUCCUUUGCUGACUAAAAUAAAAUAACUGGUGGUUUGCUAACUAUUUACCAUAUGGGUUGGCUGGUUUUUAUUAAUAAUUGUUUAGGGUAUCAUAAGAUCUGUAAGUACAAAGGAUAUUCUGUUUCUAUCUGCAAUGCAUUUGAUAAUCAUUUCUAUGAAAUGUAUUUUAUUUAAUCAGAUAAGCUAAUAAGCGAAUUGGUUACAUCGUUUGUAUCUGUUGGCCUAGUGGACAGCUGUGCCUGGUGCACCUCUGGCUUUUAAUAAAUACUCAUUGGUUGAAACACCCUGCUAACACUGUGUUUUGUCAGUUCGUAAAUUCCUUUAACCAAGACUUAACUAUGCUUUUUAACUCUUUUUCCACCUGCCAUCUACUACUACCAACUCACUUAUACUUCCUUCCUCCCAAGUAAUCAUUUCAAAACUAAAAAAGGAUUUAAGUUCUUGGGUUACAACGGUUUAAAGGAAAGAAAAUGAACUUUGAAGUCAAAAAAAAAA